ACACAUACACUCACACAUACACAACCCGGCAGGCUCGUCUGAACUUGAAGACACCCCACAUUCCAAGAUGCCCGAGGUUCCUGGGAAUGCCUGGGGUUCUUCGAUCCGGAAAAUCCUACCGGCAUCCUCCUAGGGAGGGAUUAUUAUUAUUAUUUUUCUUUAAUCUGGAAGAGAAGAGAACAAGUUGUGCUUUUCCCCCCUUCUUCUUGCUAAAUGCCAUGGAUAUAACUGAAUAAGCGGCUCAGGGCUUUCCCCGCGUGGACGUCCGAGGCCACCAUCUGCCUGCAUUCGCCGGAGCCGCCGGAGGGUUUAGCUCGAGUCUGUCUCGGGCGGGGAAGGAUGCGUGGCCGAGCCGGGGAGCCCGGGCGCCCCGCGGAGCCGGCCUCGGUGCCACCCAGCCGGGGGUAGAUGCUGCCUCGCCCAGGCGCUGAGUGACCAGACCAUGGAGACCCUGCUUGGUGGCCUGCUAGCGUUUGGCAUGGCGUUUGCCGUGGUCGACGCCUGCCCCAAGUACUGUGUCUGCCAGAAUCUGUCUGAGUCACUGGGGACCCUGUGCCCCUCCAAGGGGCUGCUCUUUGUACCCCCUGAUAUUGACCGGCGGACAGUGGAGCUGCGCCUGGGCGGCAACUUCAUCAUCCACAUCAGCCGCCAGGACUUUGCCAACAUGACGGGGCUGGUGGACCUGACCCUGUCCAGGAACACCAUCAGCCACAUCCAGCCCUUUUCCUUUCUGGACCUCGAGAGCCUCCGCUCCCUGCAUCUUGACAGCAAUCGGCUGCCAAGCCUUGGGGAGGACACCCUCCGGGGCCUGGUCAACCUGCAGCACCUUAUCGUGAACAACAACCAGCUGGGCGGCAUCGCAGAUGAGGCUUUUGAGGACUUCCUGCUGACAUUGGAGGAUCUGGACCUCUCCUACAACAACCUCCAUGGCCUGCCGUGGGACUCCGUGCGACGCAUGGUCAACCUCCACCAGCUGAGCCUGGACCACAACCUGCUGGAUCACAUCGCCGAGGGCACCUUUGCAGACCUGCAGAAACUGGCCCGCCUGGAUCUCACCUCCAAUCGGCUGCAGAAGCUGCCCCCUGAUCCCAUCUUUGCCCGCUCCCAGGCUUCGGCUUUGACAGCCACACCCUUUGCCCCACCCUUGUCCUUUAGUUUUGGGGGUAACCCACUUCACUGCAAUUGUGAGCUUCUCUGGCUGCGGAGGCUCGAGCGGGACGAUGACCUGGAAACCUGUGGCUCCCCAGGGGGCCUCAAGGGUCGCUACUUCUGGCAUGUGCGUGAGGAGGAGUUUGUGUGCGAGCCGCCUCUCAUCACCCAGCACACACACAAGUUGCUGGUUCUGGAGGGCCAGGCGGCCACACUCAAGUGCAAAGCCAUUGGGGACCCCAGCCCCCUUAUCCACUGGGUAGCCCCCGAUGACCGCCUGGUAGGGAACUCCUCAAGGACCGCUGUCUAUGACAAUGGCACCCUGGACAUCUUCAUCACCACAUCUCAGGACAGUGGUGCCUUCACCUGCAUUGCUGCCAAUGCUGCCGGAGAGGCCACGGCCAUGGUGGAGGUCUCCAUCGUCCAGCUGCCACACCUCAGCAACAGCACCAGCCGCACUGCACCCCCCAAGUCCCGCCUCUCAGACAUCACUGGCUCCAGCAAGACCAGCCGGGGAGGUGGAGGCAGUGGGGGCGGAGAGCCUCCCAAAAGCCCCCCGGAACGGGCUGUGCUUGUGUCUGAAGUGACCACCACCUCGGCCCUGGUCAAGUGGUCUGUCAGCAAGUCAGCACCCCGGGUGAAGAUGUACCAGCUGCAGUACAACUGCUCUGACGAUGAGGUACUGAUUUACAGGAUGAUCCCAGCCUCCAACAAGGCCUUCGUGGUCAACAACCUGGUGUCAGGGACUGGCUACGACUUGUGUGUGCUGGCCAUGUGGGAUGACACAGCCACGACACUCACGGCCACCAACAUCGUGGGCUGCGCCCAGUUCUUCACCAAGGCUGACUACCCGCAGUGCCAGUCCAUGCACAGCCAGAUUCUGGGCGGCACCAUGAUCCUGGUCAUCGGGGGCAUCAUCGUGGCCACGCUGCUGGUCUUCAUCGUCAUCCUCAUGGUGCGCUACAAGGUCUGCAACCACGAGGCCCCCAGCAAGAUGGCAGCGGCCGUGAGCAAUGUGUACUCGCAGACCAACGGCGCCCAGCCACCGCCUCCAAGCAGCGCACCAGCCGGGGCCCCGCCGCAGGGCCCGCCGAAGGUGGUGGUGCGCAACGAGCUCCUGGACUUCACCGCCAGCCUGGCCCGCGCCAGUGACUCCUCUUCCUCCAGCUCCCUGGGCAGUGGGGAGGCUGCGGGGCUGGGACGGGCCCCCUGGAGGAUCCCACCCUCCGCCCCGCGCCCCAAGCCCAGCCUUGACCGCCUGAUGGGGGCCUUCGCCUCCCUGGACCUCAAGAGUCAGAGAAAGGAGGAGCUGCUGGACUCCAGGACUCCAGCCGGGAGAGGGGCUGGGACGUCGGCCCGGGGCCACCACUCGGACCGAGAGCCACUGCUGGGGCCCCCUGCGGCCCGGGCCAGGAGCCUGCUCCCCUUGCCGUUGGAGGGCAAGGCCAAACGCAGCCACUCCUUCGACAUGGGGGACUUUGCUGCUGCGGCGGCGGGAGGGGUCGUGCCGGGCGGCUACAGUCCUCCUCGGAAGGUCUCGAACAUCUGGACGAAGCGCAGCCUCUCUGUCAACGGCAUGCUCUUGCCCUUUGAGGAGAGUGACCUGGUGGGGGCCCGGGGGACUUUUGGCAGCUCCGAAUGGGUGAUGGAGAGCACGGUCUAGGUGGGGGUGGGCAUGCUCCCUUUCCUGUGCGCAGGGUGGGAGAAGGGGAAAGAAUCUCACUGGCAAGUGUUUGUGGAGUUUCCAUGGUGAUGUUUACAUCCAGGGACAGUUUCGUCUCCCUGUCAAUGGCCUCGUGUCCCCCCCUACCCCGCAACACCCACAUCACCUCCCCACCACCCGGCCGGGGUGUGCUCAGGGAAUGUGGACUCGCUCAAAUGCCGGACUGAGCCCUGAGUGUUUGGAAAGGCGAGACUCCGCCUUUCUAAUCACAAAUGUAGCCUACAAGCAAGCGGCUUUGGAUUGCUUAUGGGUCUAGUGUUGUUUUUAUUUCUUAAUUUAUUUUUUUUCCAUU